GCAGCUGCGGUCGCCGCCGUCGCACGAGUCUUUCCUUAGUAACCUGGGCGAUAGCUGGUGAGUGUCCUUGACAGGGCCUCGAGGGGCGCGUGUGGUCUGGGUGCCAGAGACCCUUACUCAGGGACCUCUGGGGGACCUCAGGGGACCAGACUACCGUCCCCGACCCGUUCGAGUCCAGCUUGACCUUUAAGGCUGAGGGCGGGACCUGUGGCAUUGGAGCGAGUCUCAUGGGGUGGGGGCGGGGCUCCUUUUACCAGCUAGGAAUUUAGGGGAUGCUGGAGGAACUUACUAAAGAGUAGCCGCACACUUGACGGGAACGUUUGAGUUUCAGAACAAUCCCAUAGGAGUAGAUAUUAUUAUCUCCCAUAAUGAAGAAACGGAAGCUCACAUAGAUGAGACGGAAGUCCUGAGAGUUUGACCGAUUUAAGGUCACGUGCCUAGGAAGUGCUGGAACCAAGACUCGGAGUUUUCUCUAAGUUUAGUGCCUUUAUUUUGUUUUAAACCACACUGUUGCAUUUCCCCCCAUUUUGGAAAGCUUUAUAGUUGGAAAGAAUGAAAACCUGAUCUGACCCCUUCAUUUUAUGGUUGAAACAAAAUCUACGUAGGAGAAAUCACUUGGUACAAGUCACAAGUCAGUGGUAGAGCUGCCGCAAAUGCUUUUUGAAUACGUGUGAUUAUGAAUCUAAAUGGCAGAUGGCAGGGAGUGAUAAGUGGAUGUUUCCAAGGAUUGUCUUCAGUCAUGGCCUUGGGAUUAAAGUGCUUCCGCAUGGUCCACCCUACCUUUCGCAAUUAUCUUGCAGCCUCUAUCAGACCCGUUUCAGAAGUUACACUGAAGACAGUGCAUGAAAGACAACAUGGCCAUAGGCAAUACAUGGCCUAUUCAGCUGUACCAGUCCGCCAUUUUGCUACCAAGAAAGCCAAAGCCAAAGGGAAAGGACAGUCCCAAACCAGAGUGAAUAUUAAUGCUGCCUUGGUUGAGGAUAUAAUCAACUUGGAAGAGGUGAAUGAAGAAAUGAAGUCUGUGAUAGAAGCUCUCAAGGAUAAUUUCAAUAAGACUCUCAAUAUAAGGACCUCACCAGGAUCCCUUGACAAGAUUGCUGUGGUAACUGCUGACGGGAAGCUUGCUUUAAACCAGAUUAGCCAGAUCUCCAUGAAGUCGCCACAGCUGAUUUUGGUGAAUAUGGCCAGCUUCCCAGAGUGUACAGCUGCAGCUAUCAAGGCUAUAAGAGAAAGUGGAAUGAAUCUGAACCCAGAAGUGGAAGGGACGCUAAUUCGGGUACCCAUUCCCCAAGUAACCAGAGAGCACAGAGAAAUGCUGGUGAAACUGGCCAAACAGAACACCAACAAGGCCAAAGACUCUUUACGGAAGGUUCGCACCAACUCAAUGAACAAGCUGAAGAAAUCCAAGGAUACAGUCUCAGAGGACACCAUUAGGCUAAUAGAGAAACAGAUCAGCCAAAUGGCCGAUGACACAGUGGCAGAACUGGACAGGCAUCUGGCAGUGAAGACCAAAGAACUCCUUGGAUGAAAGUCCACUGGGGCCAGCAAUACUCCAGAGCCCAGUUUCUGCUGGAUCCCAUGGGUGGCACAUUGGGACUUCUCUCCCUCCCCCAUCUACACAGAAGACUGUCACCAUGCUGACAGAAGCCUGUCCUUGUAAGGCCCAGCCUUCCAGGGGAACACUCAGACAUGUUCAUUCUCUUCCUGCUUCUGCUCUGGGCCGGUGGGUGGCUCUCAGAAAAUACUUGCUGCUGGCAAAAGGCCUGUACUCAGGCAUUUGCUUUGACUUGAUGUUGCCAAGGGACUGAGGCCAUUGGCAGGCUUAGUACCACCUGCUCCUCAUCUUAGGAGUCUCCUUUUCAAAUAAUUAGGCUCUGUUCCCAUUUUAAAACUCUGAUAUUGGCCUUCACCUGUGACUGGACACUUUACUAGAGGCCCAUUUUCACUAAACAAUAAAAUCUAAAUAAAUUGGAAGGAAUAACAACCACAAAGGAAAGAAUAGAGUUGGUCUGGAUUGAUGAUCACUGAGGAUCUGUAUGUGAGGCACCCAUAACAGUAGUUUUGCCUGUGAGUCGUCUUCACACAUGCUGUUUUCUCUGCCUGGCUCUCUCUUCCCCUCCUUACCUGGCCAGUCCUGUUUAUCAUCAGGCCUUGUCUUGGAUAUCACGUCCUCUGGGAAGUCUUCUUUUCCCCUCUAACCUAGGACCCUCAUUACCGGCUCUCAUAGCACAGUCUACUGCUUUGUACGAAUUCUAAGUAUUCUUGUUGCACUUAAUUAGCCUGUAUAUCCUCAGAACUUUGUGUAAUGCCUGGAGCAUAGUAGGCAGUCAUAUGUUGUAUCGUGAAUAAAUUGCACAUAGUAGCUACCCAGCAAAUGCUGACUUCUUUUCUUUCUAGUCUUAACACUCCCUUUCUAUCAUUUUCCACUCUUGUACUUGUUCUCAACAUUUACUUGGUAGUGACAUACCUUUCCUGCAGGGCCUGCCCAUUGUUGACAGACAAGUAGUUUAUUGUGGCUUAUCUUCGGAUACUGGGUUAUUAGGUUUUUUUCCCUCCAAUUAUUUUUUAUUCAUUCAUUCAUUCCUAAUAUAGCCAUUAUGAGUUAGGUAUAGUUCUAGGCAUUAUUUAUAAUCUUGACAGUAAACUUAAGAGAUGUGUAUUAUCUUCAUUUACAAAUAGGAAAACUAAGUCUUGACAGUAUUAGGUAAUUUGCCCAAAGUAACAAAGCAAAGCUGAUCAGUGGUAGAAGGUUUUCAUGAUUCAUUGUCAGCGUCAUUUACAUAGAGGUGAAGUUUCUUGUGCAGGGUUACACACCUAGCAAGUAGCAGAGCUGGCAUUCAAAUUGAGGCCUGAUGUGCUAAUGUAAAAGGAAAAAAACAAACUUUUUUUCCUUUUGUACUUUCACACUCAACAUGGAACACUUCUGUGACAAGGUGUGUGAGUUUGUUUCCCCCACACACCAAGCAAUUCUCCAGCAGACACCAACUGGGUAUCCUAUAAUUCAAUUCAUUUCUGACAUUACCUGGAAAUAGUGUCAGAUCCCACAGGUUGAGGGCUCCAUCUCCCAAGACUGCCAACACUUUUGAUGCCAGUCAUGAGUCUGGGCCACCCAUACUCCUGACUGACCAACUACAAACUAGAGUCCUUGAUUUCCUUUGGUUCAGUUAAUUUCCUAGGACAGCUCACACAACUCAGGGAAACACGUUCACUGGUUUAUUAUAAAAGAUACAGCUGAACAGCCCAAUGAAGGAGGUACACAGGGCAAGGUUGAGGGAGAGGGAGAGGGUGUGGAGCUUCCAUGCCUUCUCUGGGCUCACACUCUCUCAGCACCUCACCAAUCUGGAAGGAACCACUGUGUCCUGCUGCCUUCAUUAGCAUUUAGUGAGCACCAAUUGUUUGUCAGGUGCUGAACUAUGUACUGGCAAUACAAAAAUGGGAAAGAUAUGACCCCUGUUUUGGGGGGGUACAUAGUGCACUGAACUAAAUUGCUGUCUAUAAUAAUCUAUUGGGUGGAAAAGUAGGAAGUUCAUUCCAGUUCUGCAAGGUGUCUGCUUUCAGAAUGGAGCCCACUUUGGUGGUGGCAAGGCCUGGCUGAGUUCUUUCAAAGCAACAUCCAACUUCUCUUUGCUCUUUGACUUCCUCCAGAUUCUCUCCUGUGCUGGAGGUAAUAAGGGUUGCACUUCCCUCUUUACUUACACUGGUGAAACAUGCAGUGAGGAUUCAAGGUCAAAAUUGGGUCAAAGUUAAACUAACACAGUCUCCUGCCCCACUUACCUGUCCUCUAACCCCAUCCACCAGCCCUAAGUGGUCAUCACAUGAUCAGAAGUCAGCUGGGGGAAGAGCAGGGAUAGAUAGAGCAAUUAAGGAGCCUCUUUUGGGGUAAGCCACAUGACAGGGGCUUUGCAACAGUCUUUCAUGAGUGGCCGAAAUCCCCCACUCACUGCAAAUGUGCUUCUCAAAGAUGCAGGAUUUUUUAAUAAACAGAGGAAAUGAUAAAUUAUGUUGUAAUUCCACUCCAAAGGCAUUUGGUUCUUAACAGCCAAAUCCUCUGUAGUCUUUAAAUAAACAAAAACUUAUUUGGUGAACAGACAGGGAGGAAAAUGAAAGAUUUUCUGUACUUGGGUUCCACAUGUCAACAAUUUCUCUCCUGUGUGUAUGUUGGCCAAAGCUGUAUCAUGAUAAAUGAAUAAAGGAAAACCUCGAGCCCAGGGCAGUCAGACAGCUCAGCAAAUGGCUUUCAGAUGAUUACUCAAUUUCAGUUGACAUUUAUCAAAGAGUUUCUCUGUGACUCUGUGUCAGGGCUGUAGUGGUGACAGGGACAAGAAUGAGACUACCUGUUUGGAUGUGCUGAGAAUGAGUAAUGCUGGAGCAAUUCAUUCUCCAUCUCUUCUCUCCUACAGCCUCUCUCAAAAAGAAACACUGGGUAUGGAAAUUCUCACACUUGCCAGAAGAAUUAACCACCUCUUCUAUUCAGUUUAAUGACUUUCAAAGUCCUAUGAAAUAUUCAGGCCAGAGAGAAUUUGAGAAUUUUUUUCCUGUCUGGUGUGUGUGUGUGUGUGUGUGUGUGUGUGUGUGUGUGUGUGUGUGUGUGUGUGUUGGAAAUUACAAAAUAAGUUGGAAUGCAGAAAGUUAAAAAAAAAAUCUCACCAGGCCCUACUCCUUUAAAAUUAGGUAUAUAUCUUUCCAGACCUCCUUUCUCUGUGCAUAUAUGUGUGUGUGUGUGUGUGUGUUCGUUUCAUUUUGUUUUGCCUUUGAGACAGUGUCUCACUCUGUCGCCCAUCAUGCAGUGGCACAAUCAUAGCUCACUGCAGCCUUGAACUCUUUGGCUCAUGCAAUUCUCCCACCUCAGCCUCCUGAGUAGCUGGGACUGCAGCUAUGCACCACCACACCUGGCUUUUUUUUUUUUGCUUUGUUUCCUAGGCUGGUCUCAAACACCUGGCCUCAAGCGGUCCUUCUGCCUCAGCCUCCCAAAGCGCUGGGAUUACAAGUGUGAGCCACUCUGCCUGGCCAUAUAUAAUUUUUUUUUUUUUUUUUUUGCAAUGGAGUCUUGCUCUGUCGCCCACGCUGGAGUGCAUUGGCGCAAUCUCGGCUCACUGCAACCUCUGCCUCCCUGGUUCAAGCAGUUUUCCCUGCUUCAGCCUCCUGAGUAGCUGGGAUUACAGGCGCCCGCCACCACACCCAGCUAAUUUUUUAUUUUUUUUUAGUAGAGAUGGGGUUUCACCAUGUUGGCCAGGCUGGUCUUGAACUCCUGACUCAGGUGAUCCACCUGUCUCAGCCUCCCAAAUUGCUGGGAUUACAGGCAUGAACCACUGCGCCCGGCCAUAUAAUUUUUUAGAAGGAGAGAGGGGAACUAUUCAUAUUCUGAUGUUUGCUUUUUUUUCUUACCCUGUAACAAUCAUGGUCAUCUGUCCAUGUGUGUACAUAAUAGAUACAAUUUAUUAUUUCAUUGUGAUACAGUAUUCCAUAAUAUGGGUCUACCAUAACUUAAUUCACUAUUAGCCCAUGACACUAUUUAAAAAUUAUUUCACAUGCAUUGGAGAAUGUUUAAAGAUGAUUUUUUUUUUUAAGAAAAAAGAAAGGCCCCUAUUCUAAGAUUAUCUGAUAAGGUCUGCUCUUUCUCCUUCAACCUCAGGCUAACAUUUAUUGAAUGCCUACAGUCGGCCAGGUUCCAUGCUAGACCCUUUACACGUGUUCCCACAUUGAAACUUCUGAUGAAUCCUUGUUAAUGUAGGUGUUAUGAUUAUCUGUGUUUUUCUGUGAAAAAAACAGGUUCAGAAAGGAUAUUUAACUUGCCCAAGGUCACACAGGUAGUAAGUGCUAGAAUGAAAUUUCAAACCCACAUCUGACCUUGAAGUAGGUCCUUAAUCAGUGUGCUUUGGUUCCCAAGUCUUCGCUGAACACUUACUCAAAAGGGACCUCGCGCUGUUCUGGACCUGGACGGUGAUGUGAGAGAAGCAGAAGUCUUGCUUUCAUAAAACACAUAGCAAGCUGUUCCUAAUUAAUGACUGCAAGUAAAAUAGCAUAGUACCUGGCACAUUGUAAACACCAAAGAAAUGGUAGCUCUUAUGGAGACAGUAAAGAUUACAUAUUAAUCCCCCACCUGUUUGGCCAACUUCUCUAGAAUAUGUCAGAGAGCAAGCAAAAUGUUCACCAAGCAGUGAAUAAUGAUAAUAAUAACAACAAUAACAGUAUUGACAGAUCAGUAACUAAUAUUUGCUUGGUGCUUUUUAGUUUUCAAACUGCUUCUACAUUCUUUGUUGCAUUGAAACCACUCAGUGAAACUUUGCGGUUAGACAAAGAGUGAUCAUAAAAGCUUGUAUCCUCAAAAGCCACUUUGAGGCUUUCUUUUGCCCUAAUAGACGGUCAUUUUUCAUGAUGUGCAUUUGAAAUGAUAUGUUCCCUAUUUUGGGGGUACAAAUUUUGAUAUGUAUGCAGGAAAUGUAGCUUAUAGAGUAUGUUGUUUAGGUUUUCCAUUAUUUUUUGACCCUUUGAUGAGUCUUGGACUGAAAGUGGUGUGUUUCAGACCCCUGCUAUUAACAUUUCUGUUCCUUCUUGCAUUUUCUGCUUUAUGAAAAUGGAUUCUGCUUUGUGAAAGUACUGCUGUGUUGUUUUAUACAUAGCGCUCCAGACGCUUACAUCUUCUUUAUUUCAUUCAGUGCUCUUAGUCUGAAUUUUAUCUUGUUGUAUAUCAGGAUUACAGCUCUUGCUUGCUUUUUGUUUACAUUUGCUUUCCCCAUUUCUUGAUUUUUAAGCUUUCAGAAUCACUAUUUUAGGUGUUUCUUUUUUUUUUUGGAAUUGGGUUUUGUUCGAUGAACCAUUCUGAAACUCCUUUUUUCUUAUUUUUAUUUUUAAUUGUAAAAUAUACAUAAAAUUUACUCUCUUAACCAUGUUUUUUUUUUAGACAGGGUCUUGCUCUGUCACUCAGGCUGGAUUUCAGUGGCAUGAUCUCAGCUCACUGUAGCCUUGACAACCUGGGCUGAAGCAAUCCUCCCACCUCAGCCUCCUGAGUAGCUGGGAUUACAGCCACGUGCACCGCCACACCUGGCUAACUUUUAAAAUUAUUUGUAGAGACAAGGUCUUGGCUAUGUUGCCCAGGCUGAUCUCAAACUCCUGAGCUCAGGUGAUUCUCCUACCUUGGCCUCCCAAAGUGCUGGGAUUACAGGCUUGAGCUUCUGUGCCCAGCCUUAACCAUUUUAAGUGUACAGUUCAGUAGCAUUUAGUACAUUUACAUUGUUGUACAACCAUCCUCCAGAACUCUUUACCAUGCAGAACUGACGCUCUAUACCCAUUACACAACCCCAGUUCCCCCUUCUCAGCCCCCAGCAACCACCAUUUAUGAAUUUAUAAAUUUGAUUAGGAACAUCAUGUUAAGUGGAAUCAUACAGGAUUUGUCUUUUUGUGACUAGUUUAUUUCACUGAAGCAUGAUGUCCUUAAAGUAUAUCCAUAUUGUAGCAUGUAUCAGAAUUUCCUUUCUAAGGCUGAGUAAUCUGUUGUAUAUAUGAAUAAGUAUAUAUAAAGCUCCUUUUAACAGACACUUAAAUUCAUUUACAUUUAUUUAUAAUAGUGAUAUGUUUAGUAGAACCCAUUUACUUUUUCUUUAUUUUCAGUAUUAACAUAAGUGAUUUGGUGUUUUAGCCCUAAGCAGAUAAAGGAUUAGAGAUUAGAAUGAGGAAGAGGGUUGCUUCACAUAGACGAAGUUCAGUUUUUGUGGAAUAAACAAAUAAGUGAUUAUCUCUGUCUGCCUCUUUGUCUCUCUCUCUCUCUCUUUUUUUUUUAAUAAGAGAUGAGGGGUCUCCCUAUGUUGCCCAGGCUGGACUUGAACUCCUGGGUUCAAGUGAUCCUGGAACUGCAGAUAUGCACAGCUGUGCCCGAAGAUCCCUUUCUCUUACAUUCCUUUCUUCUGGUCUGUGUUUCAGUCCAUCCUACGCUGUUAAGUUAGAACAACCUGAAACAGCUUUUAUCAUGUCACUCUUCUCUCAGAAACCUUCAUUGGUUCCCUGUUGCCUGCUGAAUUAUGUAAACUCUUCACCCUGGCAUUCAGUAACUUCUGCAAUCUGGGCCUGAUGUAUUCCUUUAAUUGUGAUGCAUCUCUUACAACUACCCUGAUACCACCAGUGCUUAAGCGAAACGGAAUUAUUAGCUUUUCUGAAAGCUAAUAAUUUUGUGCUGCUUUCUCUCACCUUCAAGCCUUUUCUUAGGCUAUUUUCUUUGCCUAGUGUAUGCUCCCUUAAACCACUUCCCCACCAGCAGGCAAAACUUACCUAGUCUUAUAAGCCCUUCUUGGUCCCAUGUUCUUCCUUACACUAACUCAUUCAUUCAUUAUCCAUCCCGAUGCUUCUCCUGAUUCAUUCAUUCAUUAUCCAUACCGAUGCCUCUCCUGAUCCCUAAACCUGCCUAUGCCUAUUAAGCGCUUGGAUUUGCCUCAAGCAUCUGACGUUCAGCUACCCACCUGCGUUUCCUCUCUCAGGAAAAGCCUCACCAUCCACCCAGGUGCCAAGCCAGGACACUGGGAGCCACUUUUGCCUCCCUGUCCCUCUCCCCUCAUCCAAUAAGUCACCAAGUCCUGUCAAUUCUCCCUUCAACAGACCUUUCCUUUCCUUCCUGGGCACACCCUUGAGUGGUGCUCACCAGGGAACAGAUGUGGCAAAUGUUCCAGGCUGGCCUCACCCGGGUCUCUAGACACUUGGCUCAGAGGCAGAACAUGGCUAACCCUAGAUAAGCCUUGUGUGAAUUCCUGGCAAGAAAGUCCCCUGCUGUCUUAGUCUGUGCAUUCUCUGACUAGCACAGUAUGUGGCGAGAGCAGGUGUUGAGGAAAUGUUUGUCUAAUUCUAAGGGGCCUGCCAGGCCUUGAUACAAAUGGCGUCACAUUUACAUGAAUAACCCAGAGUUUCUCUAAUUAUCCUCACCUGCCUGCCCAGGACCUUCAACCUCAUCUGCUAAGUCGGCCUCAGGCGUUUCUAGACAUCUUAAGGGACCGCAUGGCAUCCAAGGCCACUGGCAUCUACUGUACUCCCCUCCCACCGGCGCUUCCCUUUGCUAGCAUCUGCAGCCACAAGUGACACUUAAGGGAGAUUUACCUCCACUACUGGGAGUGUUAGUGUCUGUGACAAAAGUGCUGGUUGCUGGGCUGAGGGGGUCUGAGCAUGCUGGGUGGAAGCCCUGAAGAGGAAGGGAGAAGGUCUCUGCCCACAUCCCACAUUUGCCGUGCAUCCCUGAGUUCCAAAGCAGCCUCGCUAGGCUCUAGAGCCCCUAAAUCUCCAAAGACAGCAGCUCCUCCGCGAGCUAGCUGCCCCUGACCGAGGCUCACAGCUUGCCUAGGGGAGGGCAGGGCAAAAGUCCCUGCUAUUCUCUUCCUUUCCUGGCUCAGGCCUUGAUCCAAAUAGCUCCCUUCUUCCAAGACACUACUCCCCAGGCCUCCUCUUCCUGAUAAUAAUAGUGGCUAACAAGUUUUACUAGAUUUUAGGCAACUCAAGGAGCUAGCUGUUAUUUUGUUCAUUCUACAAGUGAGGAAGGAAGCACAGACAGUGGUUAAGUUACAUGUCCAGAGACACACAGAGGGCCUAGUGCAGUAGCUCAUGCCUGGAAUCUCAGCACUUUGGGUGGCUGAGGUGGGCGAGUCACUUGAGGUCAGGAGUUCGGGACCAGCCUGGCCAACGUGGUGAAACCCCAUCUCUACUAAAAAUAAAAAAUUUAGCCAGGUGUGGUGGCGGGCGCCUGUAAUCCCAGCUACUUCGGAGGCUGAAGCAGGAGAAUCACUUGAACCCAGGAGGCAGAGGUUGCAGUGAGCCAAGAUUGCACCACUGCACUGCAGCAUGGGCAACAGAGCGAGACUCUGUCUCCACACAGAGGAACACUUGGCAUCAGGGAGUCUGUUGUCUGACCCGCAACUAGGCAGCCUCAUACAUUAUUUUCACUAAGAGACCAGUGGGGCUGGAAAGGGACUUGUGAGGUGCUAAGUAGCCAGUGAGAGCUUCUGGGUCCUGUCGCAGUUUUGCCCUUUCUUCCCUCAAAAAAAGGUCUCUCCACUUCUCUGUGGGAAAGGCUUGGGCAAGUUCUCUGGUUUCCAAUGAGGCCAGAGAACCUGUGCUGAUCCCUAACAUCUUCACCCAUCGGGGGCAAAAUAAGUAAAAUAAAAGUAAUGUAGCAAAUGUUUUUAUAAAAGUGUUAAUUUAAAUUAACGGACUAUUACCUAUUCUUAGAGCUUUCUCUUUUGUUUUUGGCAUUAAAAUAUCCUUUCUAUUAUAAAA